AGCCUCAAAAACUCACACCAGCUCCUGCAAGGAAUGUGAAUCUUGGAGCUCCCAGCUAUUCUGUUCCUGUUUCUGUCAGCUCCUUCCCUGAAAACUCAGAGGUGCUCAGCAUGCCAUGCUAAAAGGCAAAAUAAAAAGAUCUUGGAGACAUCUCAGCUUUAAUGAGGACUUUCCAACAUUCCAGACUGCCGUCCUGCAAUGAAGCUCUGAGUCACGGUCUGUGAGGCUAAGGUACUGGCAACGGUGUGAACCCCAGGACAACUAACCUCACUAACCUUCACUCUAAGCAGAAGCCCAAAGUGAGUCUGGCCUGAAAUCAGAGCAAGCACUACAGAAAGACAUCUUUGUUAAUGGAAAGAGGAAAGAAGAAAAGAAUUUCCAAUAAGUUACAACAAACUUUUCACCAUUCUAAAGAACCCACUUUCCUUAUCAACCAAGCUGGGCUUCUCUCUAGUGACUCCUAUUCUAGCCUUUCCCCAGAAACAGAGAGUGUUAAUCCUGGUGAAAAUAUAAAGACAGACACUCAGAAAAAGAGACCUGGGACUGUGAUACUAUCAAAACUGUCAAGUAGAAGAAUUAUAUCGGAAAGCCAGCUUAGCCCCCCUGUGAUCCCGGCCCGCAGGCCUGGAUUCCGGGUAUGCUAUAUCUGUGGCCGAGAAUUUGGGUCCCAGUCAAUUGCCAUUCAUGAACCCCAGUGCUUGCAGAAGUGGCAUAUUGAAAACAGCAAGUUGCCCAAGCAUUUGAGGAGGCCAGAACCCUCCAAACCACAGUCUCUCAGCAGCAGUGGGUCCUACAGUCUUCAGGCAACUAACGAGGCUGCAUUUCAGAGUGCCCAGGCUCAGCUGCUGCCCUGUGAAUCCUGUGGCCGCACAUUCUUGCCAGAUCAUCUUCUUGUUCAUCACAGAAGCUGCAAGCCAAAGGGUGAGGGUCCCAGAGCACCACACUCAAACAGUUCUGAUCAUCUUACUGGCCUCAAGAAAGCUUGUAGUGGAACCCCAGCCCGACCAAGGACUGUUAUCUGCUACAUAUGUGGUAAGGAAUUUGGCACCCUGUCCCUUCCUAUUCAUGAGCCCAAAUGCCUGGAAAAGUGGAAAAUGGAAAAUGACCGGCUCCCUGUGGAGCUCCACCAGCCACUCCCACAGAAGCCUCAGCCCCUUCCGAAUGCACAGUCCAGCCAAGCGGGACCAAAUCAAGCUCAGCUUGUGUUCUGCCCACAUUGUAGCCGAAUCUUUACCUCAGACCGCCUCCUGGUACACCAGAGAAGUUGUAAAACUCAUCCUUAUGGGCCAAAAUAUCAGAAUUUGAAUUUAGGGAGUAAAGGAGGCCUAAAAGAGUACACUAAUUCCAAGCAGCAAAGGAACAGGGCAGCACCCAGUGUAACUGAUAAGGUAAUUCAUGCCACACAAGACGCAUUAGGUGAACCUGGUGGUGCCCUCUGCCUGUAGGGGAACAAGAGAAAACUAUCCCCAGAAUCAGCCACCUCAGCCCCUAGUAUUUUUUCUAUCAAUGCCUUGUAUCAGCCUCAAAGCAGCCUGUUCAAGUUAACUCCCUGUUGAACUCCAGGGCCUAUACCUCUCUUGGCUGAAUAGAUAUAAGAACAUCCUUGCCUGAUGGGUUCAUAUUCCUCUUCAAUUCUGCUGUCUAAAAGAAGAAGAGAUGGACUUCUUUCUUCCCUGAUCCCUGAUACAAAUAAUCCCUGGGAGAGACAGUAAUUUGAAAAUGAGUCAUUAAUGCUGUGUCUACAUUACAGAGAUAUAAUUCCCAUUCCAACAGCCAAUAUUUAUUGUCGGUUUAUUUUAGUCAUCUACCUUAGGAAUUCAUUUUUGGCAAUGCUGGGUUAUGCUGAGUUUAUCUUACUAAAAUAGAAUCUGUGUCAAAAACCCCCAAUGACUUUAGCAACAAUUAAACACUGAAGCACUUGCAAAAAUA